GCCGGAGCCCGAGCUGCAGUGCCGCCUACAAGUGGUGCGCUGGCUGCAGCUGUGGCAACCCCGGAUCCCGUCCUCCCGCCUCGCACCCAUCAGCGCGGACCCCGGGGGCGACGCAGUGGCGAAGUGGGGCUGUGGGCCCAGCGGUGGCACCAGGCGGAGAAGCACCACUCAACCCCAUCCCUGGGCUGCAGAGGGCCCAGCGCGGGGGACUCCGAGCGUCGGGAGCCUGUGGAAGAGAAGAGCGCGCGGGCGACAGUUAAACAGGCCCUGGGGCAGGGCGCGCCUCGCGCUCCAGGGAGCCCCGCCCUCCCGCGGCACCUCCGCAGCAACCGCCGCCUGCACUGGGCGCGCGAGAGCUGCUAGGGCGGUUUCUCUGCCUCGGGCCUGUUGGGCAGGGCCGGCUAAGGUGCGCGUGCUCGCUGGUUCUAACCCUUCUGUUGGGCGUUUCUGCUGAGAGGCGGGAGGCGCUGAGAGUCUGUGCGGAGGUCCGUGGACAGACUGCUUUGCUCGUUGUUGCUCUUCGGAGGCGGCGAUCCCCGAAGGCGAGCUGAAAUACGGCUGCAGGCUACAAUUUGCAGCCGACGAUUAUGGAAGACGGCAAGCGGGAGAGGUGGCCCACCCUCAUGGAGCGCUUGUGCUCGGAUGGCUUCGCAUUUCCCCAAUACCCCAUUAAACCGUAUCAUCUGAAGAGGAUCCACAGAGCUGUCUUACAUGGUAAUCUAGAGAAACUGAAGUACCUUCUGCUCACGUAUUAUGACGCCAAUAAGAGAGACAGGAAGGAAAGGACCGCCCUACAUUUGGCCUGUGCCACUGGCCAACCGGAAAUGGUACAUCUCCUGGUGUCCAGAAGAUGUGAGCUUAACCUCUGCGACCGUGAAGACAGGACACCUCUGAUCAAGGCUGUACAACUGAGGCAGGAGGCUUGUGCAACUCUUCUGCUGCAAAAUGGCGCCAAUCCAAAUAUUACGGAUUUCUUUGGAAGGACUGCUCUGCACUACGCUGUGUAUAAUGAAGAUACAUCCAUGAUAGAAAAACUUCUUUCACAUGGUACAAAUAUUGAAGAAUGCAGCAAGUGUGAAUAUCAGCCACUGUUAUUUGCUGUGAGUCGAAGAAAAGUGAAAAUGGUGGAAUUUUUAUUAAAGAAAAAAGCAAAUGUAAAUGCCAUUGAUUAUCUUGGCAGAUCAGCCCUCAUACAUGCUGUUACUCUUGGAGAAAAAGAUAUAGUCAUUCUUCUUCUGCAGCACAAUAUUGAUGUGCUUUCUCGAGAUGCGUUUCGAAAGAUUGCAGGAGAUUAUGCCAUUGAGGCUAAGAAUAGAGUCAUUUUUGAUCUAAUUUAUGAAUACGAAAGAAAGAGAUAUGAAGAUCUUCCUAUAAAUAGCAAUCCAGUGUCUUCUCAGAAACAACCAGCCUUGAAGGCUACAAGUGGCAAGGAAGAUUCUAUUUCAAAUAUAGCCACAGAAAUAAAGGAUGGACAAAAAUCUGGGACAGUGUCUUCUCAGAAACAACCGGCCUUGAAGGAUACAAGUGACAAGGAUGAUUCUGUUUCGAACACAGCCACAGAAAUAAAAGAUGAACAAAAAUCUGGGACAGUGCUUCCUGCUGUUGAACAGUGUUUAAACAGGAGUCUCUACAGACCUGAUGCUGUUGCACAGCCUGUGACAGAGAAUGAGUUUUCUUUGGAAUCUGAGAUUAUUUCAAAACUAUACAUCCCAAAGAGAAAGAUUAUUUCUCCACGAUCUAUAAAAGAUGUGCUUCCUCCUGUUGAAGAGGCUGUUGACAGGUGUCUCUACCUACUGGACCGUUUUGCACAGCCUGUGACAAAGGAUAAGUUUGCUUUGGAAUCUGAGAAUAUUUCAGAACCAUACUUUACGAACAGAAGGACUAUUUCUCAACAAUCUGCAGAAAAUUUAGAUGCUGCAUGUGGCAUUGACAAAACAGAAAAUGGAAACAUGUUUGAAGACCAAAAUGUUGAUAAGGAAGGAAAAGCACUACCAGCAACUGGACAAAAAGCAAAUGUGUCUCCUGAGCAACCGCCUUUAUUCACGCAUACGGUGAAAGACAGAGAUCACAUUUCAACUAGAUUCUUAGGAGGUAUGGAUUCACUAACUUCCAGUGAAGAAUCUUCUGAGCGACCUCCUUUAUCCACGCUUACUCUGAAAGAGGCAGAUCCCAGUUCAAAAGCAGCCAUGAGAAGGAAGGAUUCACCACCUCCAGGAAAAGUGUCUUCUCAGAAACAACCAGCUGAGAAGGCUACAAGUGACGACAAAGAUUCUGUUUCAAAUAUAGCCACAGAAAUAAAGGAGGGACCAAUAUCUGGGACAGUGUCUUCUCAGAAACAACCAGCUGAGAAGGCUACAAGUGACGAGAAAGAUUCUGUUUCAAAUAUAGCCACAGAAAUAAAGAAGGGACAACAAUCUGGGACAGUGUCUCCUCAGAAACAAUCGGCCUGGAAGGUUAUAUUUAAAAAGAAAGUUUCUCUUUUGAAUAUUGCCACAAGAAUAAUGGGUGGUGGGAAAUCUGGAACAGUGUCUUCUCAGAAACAACCAGCCUCAAAGGCUACAAGUGACAAGACAGAUUCUGCUUUGAAUAUAGCUACAGAAAUAAAGGAUGGACUACAGUGUGGGACAGUGUCUUCUCAGAAACAACCAGCCUUGAAGGCUACAACUGACGAGGAAGACUCUGUUUCGAAUAUAGCCACAGAAAUAAAGGAUGGAGAAAAAUCUGGGACAGUGUCUUCUCAGAAGCAACCAGCCUUGAAGGCUACAACUGACGAGGAAGAUUCUGUUUCGAAUAUAGCCACAGAAAUAAAGGAUGGAGAAAAAUCUGGGACAGUGUCUUCUCAGAAACAACCAGCCUUGAAGGCUACAACUGAUGAGAAAGAUUCUGUUUCGAACAUAGCCACAGAAAUAAAGGAUGGAGAAAAAUCUGGGACAGUGUCUUCUCAGAAACCACCAGCCUUGACGGCUACAAGUGACGAGGAAGGUUCUGUUUUGAGUAUAGCCAGAGAAAACAAGGAUGGAGAAAAAUCUAGGACAGUGUCUUCUCGGAAAAAACCAGCCUUGAAGGCUACAAGUGAUGAGAAGGAUUCUUUUUCGAAUAUAACCAGAGGAAAAAAGGAUGGAGAAAUAUCUAGGAAAGUGUCUUCUCAGAAACCACCAACCUUGAAGGGUACAAGUGACGAGGAAGAUUCUGUUUUGGGUAUAGCCAGAGAAAACAAGGAUGGAGAAAAAUCUAGGACAGUGUCUUCUGAGAAACCACCAGGCUUGAAGGCUUCAAGUGCCGAGAAAGAUUCUGUUUUGAAUAUAGCCAGAGGAAAAAAGGAUGGAGAAAAAACUAAGAGAGUGUCUUCUCGGAAAAAACCAUCCUUGGAGGCCACAAGUGAUGAGAAGGAUUCUUUUUCGAAUAUAACCAGAGAAAAAAAGGAUGGAGAAAUAUCUAGGAAAGUGUCUUCUCAGAAACCACCAGCCUUGAAGGGUACAAGUGACGAGGAAGAUUCUGUUUUGGGUAUAGCCAGAGAAAACAAGGAUGGAGAAAAAUCUAGGACAGUGUCUUCUGAGAAACCACCAGGCUUGAAGGCUACAAGUGAUGAGAAAGAUUCUGUUUUGAAUAUAGCCAGAGGAAAAAAGGAUGGAGAAAAAACUAGGACAGUGUCUUCUCAGAAACCACCAACCUUGAAGGCUACAAGUGAUGAGGAAGAUUCUGUUUUGAGUAUAGCCAGAGAAAACAAGGAUGGAGAAAAAUCUAGGACAGUGUCUUCUGAGAAACCAUCAGGCUUGAAGGCUACAAGUGCCGAGAAAGAUUCUGUUUUGAAUAUAGCCAGAGGAAAAAAGUAUGGAGAAAAAACUAAGAGAGUGUCUUCUCGGAAAAAACCAGCCUUGAAGGCUACAAGUGACGAGAAAGAUUCUGUUUUGUAUAUAGCCAGAGAAAAAAAGGAUGGAGAAAAAUCUAGGACAGUGUCUUCUCCGAAACAACCAGCAUUGAAGGCUAUCUGUGACAAGGAAGAUUCUGUUCCGAAUAUGGCCACGGAAAAAAAGGAUGAACAAAUAUCUGGGACAGUGUCUUGUCAGAAACAACCAGCCUUGAAGGCUACAAGUGACAAGAAAGAUUCUGUUUCGAAUAUACCCACAGAAAUAAAGGAUGGACAACAAUCUGGAACAGUGUCUUCUCAGAAACAACCGGCCUGGAAGGCUACAAGUGUCAAGAAAGAUUCUGUUUCGAAUAUAGCCACAGAAAUAAAGGAUGGACAAAUACGUGGGACAGUGUCUCCUCAGAAACAAUCGGCCCAGAAGGUUAUAUUUAAAAAGAAAGUUUCUCUUUUGAAUAUUGCCACAAGAAUAACAGGCGGUUGGAAAUCUGGAACAGAGUAUCCUGAGAAUCUGCCCACCUUGAAGGCUACAAUUGAAAAUAAAAAUUCUGUUCUGAAUACAGCCACCAAAAUGAAGGAUGUACAAACAUCCACACCAGCAGAACAAGACUUAGAAAUGGCAUCAGAGGGAGAGCAAAAGAGGCUUGAAGAAUAUGAAAAUAACCAGCCACAGGUGAAAAACCAAAUACAUUCUAGGGAUGACCUUGAUGACAUAAUUCAGUCAUCUCAAACAGUCUCAGAGGACGGUGACUCGCUUUGCUGUAAUUGUAAGAAUGUCAUAUUACUCAUUGAUCAACAUGAAAUGAAGUGUAAAGAUUGUGUUCACCUAUUGAAAAUUAAAAAUACAUUUUGUUUAUGGAAAAGAUUAAUAAAACUUAAAGAUAACCACUGUGAGCAACUUAGAGUAAAAAUUCGAAAACUGAAAAAUAAGGCUAGUGUACUACAAAAGAGAAUAUCUGAAAAAGAAGAAAUAAAAUCGCAGUUAAAGCAUGAAAUACUUGAAUUGGAAAAAGAACUCUGUAGUUUGAGAUUUGCCAUACAGCAAGAAAAAAAGAAAAGAAGAAAUGUUGAAGAGGUGCACCAAAAAGUUAGGGAAAAGUUAAGAAUAACAGAAGAGCAAUAUAGGAUAGAAGCUGAUGUGACAAAACCAAUUAAACCGGCUCUCAAAUCAGCAGAGGUGGAAUUGAAGACAGGAGGAAAUAAUUCAAAUCAGGUUUCUGAAACUGAUGAAAAAGAAGACCUGCUGCAUGAAAACCGCUUGAUGCAAGAUGAAAUUGCCAGGCUCAGGCUGGAAAAAGACACAAUAAAAAACCAAAACCUGGAAAAGAAAUACUUAAAAGACUUUGAAAUUGUGAAAAGAAAGCAUGAAGACCUUCAAAAGGCUCUAAAACGGAAUGGGGAAACAUUAGCAAAAACGAUAGCCUGUUAUAGUGGACAGCUUGCUGCUCUGACAGAUGAAAACACAACGCUCCGUUCCAAACUGGAGAAGCAAAGAGAGAGCAGGCAAAGACUGGAAACAGAAAUGCAAUCAUACCAUUGUAGACUGAAUGCUGCUCGAUGUGAUCAUGAUCAAAGUCACUCAUCAAAAAGAGACCAAGAGCUUGCUUUCCAGGGCACAGUAGAUAAAUGUCGUCACUUACAGGAAAAUUUGAAUUCUCAUGUUCUGAUUCUUUCUCUGCAACUUUCUAAAGCUGAGAGUAAGUCCAGAGUCCUCAAAACUGAGCUCCAUUACACAGGAGAGGCUCUGAAAGAAAAGGCUUUGGUUUUUGAACACGUGCAAAGUGAGCUAAAGCAAAAACAGAGUCAAAUGAAGGACAUUGAAAAAAUGUACAAAAGUGGAUACAAUACAAUGGAAAAAUGCAUAGAAAAACAGGAAAGAUUUUGUCAACUAAAAAAACAAAAUAUGUUGCUUCAACAGCAACUGGAUGAUGCUCGCAACAAAGCUGACAAUCAAGAAAAAGCAAUACUUAAUAUUCAAGCCAGAUGUGAUGCUAGAGUACAAAACCUUCAAGCUGAGUGCAGAAAGCACCGUCUUUUACUAGAAGAAGACAAUAAAAUGUUGGUCAAUGAACUGAAUCAUUCGAAAGAAAAAGAAUGCCAAUAUGAAAAAGAGAAAGCAGAAAGAGAAGUAGCUGUGAGACAGCUUCAACAAAAACGAGAUGAUGUCUUAAACAAAGGAUCAGCAACAAAAGCUCUGCUGGAUGCUUCAUCGCGUCACUGCACCUAUUUAGAAAAUGGGAUGCAGGAUUCAAGGAAGAAAUUAGACCAGAUGAGAAGUCAAUUUCAAGAAAUACAGGAUCAACUUACAGCUACUAUAAGAUGUACUAAGGAGAUGGAAGGCGACACACAAAAGCUUGAAGUAGAACAUGUGAUGAUGAGAAAAAUUAUUAAAAAACAGGAUGACCAAAUUGAGCGGCUUGAGAAAAUCCUGCAGCAUUCAAGUUUGAUGCUGCAGGUGUUUGAGAGCUAGAUGAAGGUAUGUUGCCAAAAUUUAUGAAUUAAAUUCAAAUCAUUGAUUUCUGAAAUAAACUCUAAGUAGUGAACGGUAUUCCCUCUCAAUUGCUUGGUUAAUAAAUGCUACAUUAAAUAUUUUUUCUUACACACAUCUAGUGAAAGAUGUGAAAACAUAAACAUUCAUAGUGAAGGGUAUACUUAUGCUUUGUUAAUUCAUCAUGUUUCAUAGCUUUAAAAAAAUCGCAAGAAAUCUGUGUAUCCCUUUUUUUCUGGCCCUACACUUUUCUUCUGCCACCCCUAUAGACUAUCAGCCUGCACACUGAAACUGUUCUCACAAAACAAAGGCAUUAUCAACUUCUCAAGGUUAAGGUAGUGAUUUAAGGCUAACAGACCCCACACUCAUGUGAUAAUAAUUAGUUAAGCAAUUACAGGUCACAAGCAGUCACUUGACCAGUGACAUUUUAAAUCUCUAGUCAUUGACUUUGUCAUUGGUUUACUUUUGCCCCUGGGAAAAGUUGAAAAUUCCUUAGCAUGGAAUCAAAACUCUCACAUCAGUGUGGUUCUUGUCAAGUUAUUCAGCCUUAUCUUUCGCCACUUACCAUACUCUACACCUUUGUUCUAGCAUCCAGCCAAACUAGACUACAUGGAGCUCCACAGUGAUCGUCUUCACCUCCAGCUGUUUGCAUUUACUUCUUCCCUCUAUCCUACAUGUGUUUUCCUUCCCCUUCAGAUAUCAACCUAUGAAUUGCCUCUACCAAAAAGCCUACAAUAUUGACACAAACCUGGGCUAGUAUCCCUUCUAUGUCUUCCAAUAAGUGCUGUCUUAUGCUUGUCAUUGUAUGUAUGACUCUGUAUGGGAAUUGCCUGUUUGUUUUUUCAGAUUAUAGCAUACAGUUGUUGAGGGGCGGACCGUAUCAUCUUUAUCUUGUAAUUCCAGUGCUUGUCCUAGUACCUUAGCACAUGGUUGCUGAAUACAUGAACGAAGAGUGAGAAACCAGAAGCUCUGAUACUUAACUGCCAUGAUAAUGAAUUCGGUGUGCAACUAUGGGCAAAUUAUAUUUAAUAGUAAUUGCAUAUUGUACAUAUUUUUCAUUCUUAUUAACACUGAUAAGCUUUUCAGCAUAUACUGACUUUCUCUUAGUUAACUGUGAAAUCAUUUAGAUAAAGAAUAUAAUUCUUUUUCAUUCUAACUUCUGAAUUUAAAUCUGAAUCCUCUAUAGCAGGGGUCCCCAACUCCCAGGCCACACACAGUUCCAUGACCUGUUAGGAAGCAGGCUGCACAGCAGGAGGUGAGUGGCAGGCAAGCGAGUGAAGCUUCAUCUGUAUUUCCAGCCACUCCCUGUUGCUCACAUUAUCACCUGAGCUCUGCCUCCUGUCAGAUCAGCAAAGCCAUUAGAUUCUCACAGGAGUGAAAAUCCUACUGUGAACUGCUCGUUCAAGGGAUCUAGGUCACAUGCUCCUUAUGAGACUCUAAUGCCUGAUGAUAUGUCAUUGUCUCCUAUCUCUUCACGAUGGGACCAUCUAGUUACAGAAAAACAAGCUCAGGACUCCCAUUGAUUCUCCAUUAUGAUGAGUUGUGUAAUUAUUUCAUUAUGUAUUACAAUGUAGUCAUAAUAGGAAUAAAGUGCACAAUAGAUGUAAUACGCUUGAAUCACCAUCCUGAAACCAUCCCCCAAACCCCCAUCUGUGGAAAAAUUAUCUUUCACAAAACUGCUGCCUGGUGCCAAAAAGGCUGGGGACUGCUGCUCUAUAGCUUCUGCACUAGAAUCUACUAAUGAGUAAAAUUUAAAUCAAUAACUAGUUUUAAAAGCAUAACAAGAAUAUGUGCUGUCUGGCUGCAGUGGCUCAUGCCUGUAUUCUCAGCACUUUGGGAGGCCAGUGCAGGUGGAUCACUUGAGGUCAGGAGUUCAAGACCAGCCUGGCCAAUAUGGUGAAAUCCUGUCUCUACUAAAAAUACAAAAAUUAGCUGGGUGUGGUGGUGCAUGCCUGUAGUCUCAGCUACUCGGGAGGCUGAGGUGGGAGAAUCACUUGAACCCGGGAGGCAGAGGUUUCAGUGAGCCAAGAUCGUGCCACUGCACUCCAGCCUGAGCAACAGAGUGACUCCAUCUCAAAUGCAAAACAAAACAGAAAGAAUACAUGCUGACGAAAAAAAUCUAAGACAAUAAAAUUGUAUUACUAGGCUGUUAACAUGAUAUUUUGUUUCCCGUUAAAUGUGUGACAUGCAAAAGUAUUUAUUAAAUGAAAAUAUUUUUUAUCUUUUAUGUCUGAUGAAAAUUUAUAUCGUGUUUUAAAUGAUGUUUCUUGGCCUCUUUAACUUUUUAUUUUUUUAUUAUUUUUUUUUUGAGACGGAGUCUGGCUCUGUCACCCAGGCUGCAGUGCAGUGGCGAGAUCUUGGCUCACUGCAAGCUCCGCCUUCUGGGUUCACGCGGUUCUCCUGCCUCAACCUCCCGAGUAGCUGCGACUACAGGUGCCCAGCUAGUUUUUUUUUGUAUUUUUAGUAGAGAUGGAGUUUCUCCCUGUUAGCCAGGAUGGUCUCCAUCUCCUGACCUUGUGAUCUGCCCACCUCGGCCACCCAAAGUGCUGGGAUUACAGGUGUGAGCCACUGCACCGAGCCUGAAAAUCUUACUACCUAAAUAACUUCCCACUCCACUCACACCCACAAUCUUUCUAUAAUCCACAUUCUCUCCUGAGACAAGAGCUUGGGAAGUUCCGUCUUGCUGAGGGAACUUUAUAUUGUUCAGGAAUUCUUUAAUAAGGUUUUACAUAGUUGGGGAAACCAGGGAAAAGCAGGUUUGUCACUGCUUUGCUGAGGAGCAGACUCACGUGCCUUGGAAGAAUUUAGUAAACCUUCAAUAGAUGGCCUAAGAUACUAACAGGGGCCAUCUCAUUAAGCUACACAGUUAUUUAUAAAUGAAAGUAUAAUCUAGAACUUACAUGUCAAAGUCUUCCACUAGAAAGAUGGCAAUAUUUGACUAAAACUGCAAAGUUUGUCCCAGUUGACAAAACUCUAAUCAAGCCCCUGCCCUUCUCAUUCUGUUUUUCCUUUUAAACUUUUUCUUAUAUUUUAAUUUUUCAUUUGACAAAUGCAUAUUUCCUCUUUAUACCAUGCUUCCAAGUGUCACUCUGAUACAUACCUUCAAUGAGCAGACACAGGAUUGUGGAGUUUGUUGUGGACACUCAUCCCAUGAAUAGGGAGACUCCGAUAACCUGAACAGACGGCUCUAGAAAAGAAAGGAAACUUUCUUUUCCUUCCAUACAGAGCUUCCCCCCAUUAUUUCAGUGUACACAAACCAACAUCAGUUCUUUAACACAAAAAUAAAAAUACUCAAGAUCAAGCAAUUGUGAGGGGAAUCAUCUUUCCAGAAGUCAAUUCUUCUAGCGGCUACCUUCAGCAUAUACAACUUGAAUAAAAAGAAGUUGGUCAAACGAGUAAAACUUUCCCACCUCAUUCCAGUUCUAUCUACCCAUUGACAACACCUUCGGUCUUCUCACAAAUAUUGAGUAGAAACACUGCCAACUCUUCACCUUUAUCUGGCUCAUUCCCAGAGCCAGGAGAAGAUGUGACUUAUUUGGUGGAUGGGAAAUCUUAUCCAUUGGUCCCAUCAAAUCCAUUGGUCCACGUUUGCCUAUUAGUAAGGCAAACUUACUCAGUGAUCAAUGAGUACAUCUAGUCUCUCUUUCUCCUCUGGAUUCUGAACAGGAGACUUGGAAGGCAGGUGAAGACCCUCCCUGCACUGGGUGGGUAACUGACUGUUCUUCAGAUGAACUUUUUUUUGUUCAGGUUCUAAAGUCAAGGCUAGGGGGCAAUAUUAGAAGUCUUUUUUGGUCAACAUUAAGCCAUAGUUUCUAAAUCAGCUUUAGGAGGAAUAAUGUAUUUGGAUAUUGAUCUGACCUUUUGUUUUUAUUUCUAAGUUGGUUUGGCACUGAAAAAGGAGAGGUUUGUUAUCAGUCCACACCCCUAAUGCCCUGACAUCCAUGAAUCCGUUUUAGUGGAAUCCAGAUCUCUAAGAAAGAGAUAUAAAAUAUUUGUUCCUAUCCAACUGUGAUUACUGUAUUUCCAACUAUGUUGCUGUCGGUAAGUAGAGUCUGCAUACAUGUUUCUGGUUCAUAUAUGCCUAGGGUUCCAGAGCAUUACAUUUCCAUCAAAAUGUAGAUCCCGAGAAUGCCAGAGAGGGUCAGGCCGAGGAUAGAACAGACAGUGAUUUUCAGAUACUGCAGUAGGAAGGUGGAUCCAUGUCUUGGCUGGUACUUGUAACCAUGAAGUGUGGGAAAGUAAUGACCAGAUUGAGUAAAUGACCAGAAAUUCAAAACUAAGCCACAAGAAAUUUGUCUAUUUCUGCUUUUGUUGACUGCUAUCAGGGUUGCAUCAAAAACAGUAUUGCUGAGACCAGUGUUGUGGAGCUUUAACUCUAUGUUUUCUUCUAGUAAUUUUACAGUUCAGGCCUUCUAUUUAAAUCUUCAUUUGGAGUUGAUAUUAGUAUGUGGUGUAAGUUAAGGGACUAACUUUAUUUUUCCUGUGGAUAUUCAGUUUUCUCAACACCAUUUGUAGAACAGACUAUCCUUUAACCAUUGUAUGUCCUUGGCACCUUUGUCAAAGAUAAGUUGACGUGUGUGGAUUUAUUUCUGGGUUUUCCAUUUUGUUUAGCAAAUUUGUCCAUUUAUAUGCCACUACCAUGAUUACAAUUGUUUUACAAUAUGUAAUAAAAUUAGGUAGCAUGCUGUCUCUAGCUUUGUUCUUUUUGCUCAAGAUUAUUUUGUCUAUUUUAGGUCUGUUCAAUACAAAUGUCAAGAUUUUUUUCCAUUUCUGUAAAAGAAUGGCAUUGGAAUUUUGAUAGUGAUUGCAUCAAAUAUGUUGCUUUUGGUAUUUUGUUCAUUUUCACAAUAUUAAUUCAUCCCAUCCACAAGCAUGAAUUUUUUUUUCAUUUACUUGUGUUUUUAAAUUUUUGUUCAUUGGUGUUUUAUAGUUUUUCAUAUACAGGACCUUUAAUUUUUUGCUUAAAUUUACACCUAAGUAUUUAAUUUCUGUUGCUAUCAUACUUGGGAUUUUUAAAAAAUUUCUUCAGGUAGUUUGUUAUUUGUAUACAGAAACACUUCUGAUCUUUGUUAGAUUAUUUUGUAUCCUGAAACCUUAUCGAAUUCAUGCAUCAGUUCUAACAGUUUUUGGUGGAAUAUUUAGGGUUUUCUGUAUACAGGAUCAUGUUGUCUGCAAUUAGAGAUAAUUUCACUUUUUUCUGAGUAGGAUGCUUUUCUUUUCUUGUCUAAUUGUUCUGCCUAGGAAUUCCACUGUUAACGAUGAAAAGAAGUGGUGAGACUGGUCAUCCUUGUCUUGUCUCUGAACAUGGAGGAAAAGCUUUCCACUUUUCACUGUUGAGAAUAAUGUUAGCUAAGAGCUUGUCAUACACGGUUCUUUUUUGUGUCGAGAUACAUUUUCUCUACACUUAAUUUGUUGAGAGCUUUCAUCAUGAAAGGGUUUUAAAUUUUGUCAUGUGCUUUUUCUGCAUGUAUUGAGAGAAUCGUAUGAUUUUUGUCUUUGACUUUGUUCAUGCAUUUUAUCACAUGUAUUCAUAUGCAUAUGUUGAAACCAACUUGCAUCCAAAGGAUAAAUCCCACUUUAUCAUGGUGAAUGAUUCCAUUCAUAUAUUCUUAAAUUUGGUUGCUAAUGUUUUGUUGAAGAUUUUUGAAUCAGGGUUCGUUACUGACAUUGGCCUAGUAUUUUCGUCUCUUGUAGUGUCCUUGUCUGUCUUUGGUAUCGGAAUGAUGGUACCCUAAUAAAAUGAGUUUGGAAGUA